AGACGGCCCGGAUCCCGGUUACCGGCCCCUCGCUCGCUGCUCGCCAGCCCAGACUCGGCCCUGGCAGUGGCGGCUGGCGAUUCGGACCGAUCCGACCUGGGCGGAGGUGGCCCGCGCCCCGCGGCAUGAGCCGGUGACCAAGCUCGGGGCCGAGCGGGAGGCAGCCGUGGCCGAGAGCUACUCAGAGUUGCUGUUUCUCCUUGAGAUGCUUUUGGUGUUGGGGAACCACUGAUUCAAGUAUACACAUAGACCUUGAGAGCUUCUUGGGAAGUUCUAACAUGGGCCAGCGGAGGGCAGCUCCUUGCCUGCAUUUGUCCCAAAACUUCCUGUCUUCAAACUCCAGGAGGGAUAUGCAGAAUGGCAAGGAAGCCAUACCAUAGGGAGUGUGAGGAAGAGGCUGUCUGUGUCAUUAUGUGUGCGUCGGUCAAGUAUAAUAUCCGGGGUCCUGCCCUCAUCCCAAGAAUGAAGACCAAGCACCGAAUCUACUAUAUCACCCUCUUCUCCAUUGUCCUCCUGGGCCUCAUUGCCACUGGCAUGUUUCAGUUUUGGCCCCAUUCUAUCGAGUCCUCAAAUGACUGGAAUGUAGAGAAGCGCAGCAUCCGUGAUGUGCCGGUUGUUAGGCUGCCAGCCGACAGUCCCAUCCCAGAGCGGGGGGAUCUCAGUUGCAGAAUGCACACGUGUUUUGAUGUCUAUCGCUGUGGCUUCAACCCAAAGAACAAAAUCAAGGUGUAUAUCUAUGCUCUGAAAAAGUACGUGGAUGACUUUGGCGUCUCUGUCAGCAACACCAUCUCCCGGGAGUAUAAUGAACUGCUCAUGGCCAUCUCAGACAGUGACUACUACACUGAUGACAUCAACCGGGCCUGUCUGUUUGUUCCCUCCAUCGAUGUGCUUAACCAGAACACACUGCGCAUCAAGGAGACAGCACAAGCGAUGGCCCAGCUCUCUAGGUGGGAUCGAGGUACGAAUCACCUGUUGUUCAACAUGUUGCCUGGAGGUCCCCCAGAUUAUAACACAGCCCUGGAUGUCCCCAGAGACAGGGCCCUGUUGGCUGGUGGCGGCUUUUCUACGUGGACUUACCGGCAAGGCUACGAUGUCAGCAUUCCUGUCUAUAGUCCACUGUCAGCUGAGGUGGAUCUUCCAGAGAAAGGACCAGGUCCACGGCAAUACUUCCUCCUGUCAUCUCAGGUGGGUCUCCAUCCUGAGUACAGAGAGGACCUAGAAGCCCUCCAGGUCAAACAUGGAGAGUCAGUGUUAGUACUCGAUAAAUGCACCAACCUCUCAGAGGGUGUCCUUUCUGUCCGUAAGCGCUGCCACAAGCACCAGGUCUUCGAUUACCCACAGGUGCUACAGGAGGCUACUUUCUGUGUGGUUCUUCGUGGAGCUCGGCUGGGCCAGGCAGUAUUGAGCGAUGUGUUACAAGCUGGCUGUGUCCCGGUUGUCAUUGCAGACUCCUAUAUUUUGCCUUUCUCUGAAGUUCUUGACUGGAAGAGAGCAUCUGUGGUUGUACCAGAAGAAAAGAUGUCAGAUGUGUACAGUAUUUUGCAGAGCAUCCCCCAAAGACAGAUUGAAGAAAUGCAGAGACAGGCCCGGUGGUUCUGGGAAGCGUACUUCCAGUCAAUUAAAGCCAUUGCCCUGGCCACCCUGCAGAUUAUCAAUGACCGGAUCUAUCCAUAUGCUGCCAUCUCCUAUGAAGAAUGGAAUGACCCUCCUGCUGUGAAGUGGGGCAGCGUGAGCAAUCCACUCUUCCUCCCGCUGAUCCCACCACAGUCUCAAGGGUUCACCGCCAUAGUCCUCACCUACGACCGAGUAGAGAGCCUCUUCCGGGUCAUCACUGAAGUGUCCAAGGUGCCCAGUCUAUCCAAACUACUUGUCGUCUGGAAUAAUCAGAAUAAAAACCCUCCAGAAGAUUCUCUCUGGCCCAAAAUCCGGGUUCCAUUAAAAGUUGUGAGGACUGCUGAAAACAAGUUAAGUAACCGUUUCUUCCCUUAUGAUGAAAUCGAGACAGAAGCUGUUCUGGCCAUUGAUGAUGAUAUCAUUAUGCUGACCUCUGACGAGCUGCAAUUUGGUUAUGAGGUCUGGCGGGAAUUUCCUGACCGGUUGGUGGGUUACCCGGGUCGUCUGCAUCUCUGGGACCAUGAGAUGAAUAAGUGGAAGUAUGAGUCUGAGUGGACGAAUGAAGUGUCCAUGGUGCUCACUGGGGCAGCUUUUUAUCACAAGUAUUUUAAUUACCUGUAUACCUACAAAAUGCCUGGGGAUAUCAAGAACUGGGUAGAUGCUCAUAUGAACUGUGAAGAUAUUGCCAUGAACUUCCUGGUGGCCAACGUCACGGGAAAAGCAGUUAUCAAGGUAACCCCACGAAAGAAAUUCAAGUGUCCUGAGUGCACAGCCAUAGAUGGGCUUUCACUAGACCAAACACACAUGGUGGAGAGGUCAGAGUGCAUCAACAAGUUUGCUUCAGUCUUCGGGACCAUGCCUCUCAAGGUGGUGGAACACCGAGCUGACCCUGUCCUGUACAAAGAUGACUUUCCUGAGAAGCUGAAGAGCUUCCCCAACAUUGGCAGCUUAUGAAACGUGUCAUUGGUGGAGGUCUGAAUGUGAGGCUGGGACAGAGGGAGAGAACAAGGCCUCCCAGCACUCUGAUGUCAGAGUAGUAGGUUAAGGGUGGAAGGUUGACCUACUUGGAUCUUGGCAUGCACCCACCUAACCCACUUUCUCAAGAACAAGAACCUAGAAUGAAUAUCCAAGCACCUCGAGCUAUGCAACCUCUGUUCUUGUAUUUCUUAUGAUCUCUGAUGGGUUCUUCUCGAAAAUGCCAAGUGGAAGACUUUGUGGCAUGCUCCAGAUUUAAAUCCAGCUGAGGCUCCCUUUGUUUUCAGUUCCAUGUAACAAUCUGGAAGGAAACUUCACGGACAGGAAGACUGCUGGAGAAGAGAAGCGUGUUAGCCCAUUUGAGGUCUGGGGAAUCAUGUAAAGGGUACCCAGACCUCACUUUUAGUUAUUUACAUCAAUGAGUUCUUUCAGGGAACCAAACCCAGAAUUCGGUGCAAAAGCCAAACAUCUUGGUGGGAUUUGAUAAAUGCCUUGGGACCUGGAGUGCUGGGCUUGUGCACAGGAAGAGCACCAGCCGCUGAGUCAGGAUCCUGUCAGUUCCAUGAGCUAUUCCUCUUUGGUUUGGCUUUUUGAUAUGAUUAAAAUUAUUUUUUAUUCCUUUUUCUACUGUGUCUUAAACACCAAUUCCUGAUAGUCCAAGGAACCACCUUUCUCCCUUGAUAUAUUUAACUCCGUCUUUGGCCUGACAACAGUCUUCUGCCCAUGUCUGGGAACACACGCCAGGAGGAAUGUCUGAUACCCUCUGCAUCAAGCGUAAGAAGGUCCCAAAUCAUAACCAUUUUAAGAACAGAUGACUCAGAAACCUCCAGAGGAAUCUGUUUGCUUCCUGAUUAGAUCCAGUCAAUGUUUUAAAGGUAUUGUCAGAGAAAAACAGAGGGUCUGUACUAGCCAUGCAAGGAGUCGCUCUAGCUGGUACCCGUAAAAGUUGUGGGAAUUGUGACCCCCAUCCCAAGGGGAUGCCAAAAUUUCUCUCAUUCUUUUGGUAUAAACUUAACAUUAGCCAGGGAGGUUCUGGCUAACGUUAAAUGCUGCUAUACAACUGCUUUGCAACAGUUGCUGGUAUAUUUAAAUCAUUAAAUUUCAGCAUUUACUAAUACUGCACAUGUGUGAAUUAUACCUCUUUAAGCCCAGUUGAUGAACAAAUCUACCCUGGCGAAUGUUAAAUGUUAUGGAUUCGAAACAGAUUUAUCUGGCUCUGAUAUUAAGAUUAGCCACAGUUUGGGCUUUAGCCACAACAUAUGUCCCCAAAACACAAAAUACAUAACAAUUUGCUUAGAAUAUGGAUAUAAUUACAGAAACCUAGUUGUUUUGCCAGUCAGCGUCAGUCAUACACCAUCCAUUGUUCUGUUGAGUGACAUGAAGGUGGGCAGUUAUUAUGCUGUAGUUUCAUCAAGAGUCACUUCAGAUGUGUUCCCCAGACUUUGAGAGGUCAAAGAAAGUUUCAGAAGUAGCAAAGUUGGAAGUGGAAAUCAUAAGAGUUUUGUCUUCUUUCAUUUGAAUAAGUGAUCGAAUCAUGGACUAUUAUUGCCAAAGGGGGCAAGCGAUCAUCUCAUCCAGUUUGUUCAUUUUGCAAAUGCAGAAACUGAAGCUGCAGAUGUUCAUUUUGCAAAUGCAGAAACUGAAGUGAUUUUUUUCAGUUUCUGACAGCAGCAAACACAGGUGCUUACCAAAUACUUUUGAUUUGGGUAAUGUGUACUGGUCAGUAGGAGACAUGGGAAAGCAUUUUGGUCUCAUGUAUUCAUAAUAUUGGGGACGAUAUGGUAGAAAGCCAGGAAAAAUAUUUCUGUUGUCACCCAGGUACCAGAGGCUGACAAGCACAGUGAGGACCUCUAAUCUUUCUAGGGGUUUUCUAGUUUGUUUUCCAAGAUGUGGGGCAGGUAUAGGGGAGGGUCUUACAUUGAAAUCUCUGCUGAAAGCUAUGGACUGUGCUGGCAUUGUGUAUGUGUCAUAUUGCCCUGGUUUCUUCAAAUUUCUGCCCUUUUGCUCAUCAUCGAAUGCACUACCUUAGUGGCUGGUUUCUAAUGCAGCUUCUCUCCCAAAGGGUACAUUUUUAAAUUUUUAUUUUUUAAAAUCUUGAGAGUCCUUUGAUUUGGGAAGAGGAACUCUUUCAUCUGAGUUCAUUGUGAGCCCUAGAGAGCUGUGUGACUUUAUCAUCGUCAUAGGAGUCAUUGGACUUUAAAGGCAUUACAACUCCAUUUAAAGUACCUCAUUACUCCCAGGAAUAUUGGGUGUUAGAUCUUGCAACACAGCAUAAAACAAUUUAUGUUAAAGAAGGAGCAUUAUAUCCUAGGCACUUGAAACAACCUCAAAGGUGAUGUUACCCUAUGAACAGAUAGGUGGUACAGUCACCGUAGAAAUUCAAGACAGGGAUAUAGCAGGUGAUGGCGAUUCAUGGAUUCAGAGUGGGCUAGGGACUCCACUUUAUUGUUCGUGUAUUUCUGAGCUGCUAACCAGCAAACCUCACCCAUAAGCUUAGGUCAGGAUCAUCUGUCCUCGGGAUGCCAUAGAGCCUGGUUUCAGAAGCAGAACAAUCAUGCUAAUUAAAAUGUCGUGUUCUGGCCUACAGCAGACAACAGCUGGUUUUAGAUUAAGAAAUCUUUUUAAAGAAACACAUCUUACUGGCCUAUAGAGAAGACGAACUUGAACUGGCCCUGGCCCAAGUGCACACUGAGCCACUGGCUUUGCCCCCAGGGGCCUAACUGGGAUGGGCCUGCUUGGAAUGCCAGGGCUGGAAAUACUUUUUUAUUUUGCUGAUUAACAUUACAUAGUUGUUAAAAUGUUUAUCUCAUGUAUUUUACCAACCCUCACACAUUUAGGUAUAAACCUCCUUUUCUGGGAGAAUUAAAGAGAAAAACAGCAACUUUAGUUGUCAGAAUCUUGUGUUCUUUCCUGCCAGUGAUGCUCUGCUGUAUCCUUUUUUUUUUUUUUUUUUUUGAGACAGAGUCUUGCUCUUGUCACCCAGGCUGGAGUGCAACAAUAGCAUGGUCUCGGCUCACUACAUCCUCCGCCUCCCAGGUUCAAGUGAUUCUCCUGCCUCAGCCUCCUGAGUAGCUGGGAUUACAGGCGCUUGCCACCACGCCUGGCUAAUUUGUUUGUAAUUUUAGUAGAGGCAGGGUUUCACCACGUUAGCCAGGCUGGUCUCGAACUCCUGACCUCAGGUGAUCUGCACGCCUUGACCUCCCAAAGUGCUGGGAUUACGGGCGUGAGUCCCCACGCUCAGCCACUGUAUCCUUUACUCAGUGUCAUCAAGUUCAAAGCUCUGACCACCCUGGUUUCUCUGCCAAAGCCUCAUCUACUUCCAGCUGGGCUUUGAACUUGUGGUUUUUAAGUGCUGGUUUCUCUGCUGCCUUUGGAAAAUAGUGACCAUCAUGCUGGUCUGUGCUGACGCAGACUGGGAGCUGGAAGAGACAAGCUCCCUCUUUGCUCUCAUUGGCCAAAGAUGUUGCUAAUAACCCUGUGAUCCUAGCUUCCUUCUAGGAUGAUAGCCUCUGACAGGCACCAUGCCAGGAGGAAACUAGAGCGUCUUUAUCACUGAAAGAUAGCACGUUUCUAGCCACAGGUUCUGAAGUUGAUUUGAGGUUAAAAUCCAAGAACCUUUGAUAGUUUUCAGCCAAGAUAGUAAUCAGAAAGUAGAUGAAGCAGAGACUGGGUUUGGGAAGUGGUUGGGUUCUGGGAAGGCUCUUCCUAGCUCUGCAGUUAGAUCCUGUGAGGACCCAGCUGAUAGAGUAAAGGCUUUGGGUGUUGGAGACUUCCCAUCAGCCACCCAUCAUGAGCCUGGUGUGUUUCCUUUGCUUUGUAGCUCCUUUGGGGGUAUGCUGCUUUUUCCAUUUCUCUUGGCUCGGGUACUCUUCCAUUGCAGCAAGAGAAGCCACAGUGGGCUGUUCCCCAAGCAGCCCUGGCACAGAGAGGCAGAGUAGAGAAUGCUAAACUGGCCCCAUGUCUCCUCCAGCCACUUCCUGAGGAGCAGUUCUGGCAGGAGUGUUAACCAUAUUGGCAGCAGCUUCCAUCCAGAGAGACUUUGAAAGCAACUUGAGCUUUCCACUGCAGGGCCUGGAGGCAUAUGAAACCUGUGGGGCCUGCCCCUACUCACCUCACCCCUGAGCUCUGUCCAAGCCCUGGACCUCCUGUCCUCGGCCUGUGUUUGGUACUCACCCACUUUCUACUUCUGAGUAGAAUCAAGGGCAGCAUUUGGUCCCAUUAUACCAGCCAUGCAUCAUCUGUGAACAGGCCUUAUUGAGCUUAUCUUGGCAGAGGAAAGUCAGGCAGGCAAGACCCACUCUAAAUUUUAAUGUUUCCCCCUCAUUUUAGGGUGGGAGCUGUGAGUUCAUCUGAAGACUGGGUGAGGGCAUUGUAAGCUCAAGCCACAGCCUCUUUUCCACCUCCAUUAAAUGGACUGUUAGGGAUGCCCAGCUUCCCCAAUUUCCUGGGAGGGUGUGUGGGUCUGUACAGGCAACCUUGUGUCAUUCUUUCAAUUUCCGGCUCACCAUUGCUGGCAACAGUGGGAAGAUGACCAGAGAAAGUUUGGCCCCCUCUCCCAAGCUUCCAGGCCUCUUUCCUUUUCAAGAAAUAGUUGAGUCACCAGCAUCUGUAUCUGGCAUUUUGUUUCUUCACAUUUGCAACCAUUUCAGGGUAGAGUUUUUUUGUUUGUUUGUUUGUUUGUUUUUGUUUUUUUUGUUUUUUCUUUGGAAACAGAGUCUCACUCUGUCCCAUAGGCUGGAGUGUAGUGCUGUGAUCAUGGCUCGCUGCAGCCUCAAACUCCUGGACUCAAGCAGUCUUCCCAUCUCAGCCUUCCAAGUAGCUGAGACUAAAAGCGUGCACCACCACACCUGGCUGAUCUUUUAAUUUUUUUGGAGAGACAGGGCCUCACUAUGUUGCCUAGGCUGGUCUCUAACUCCUGGGAUCAAGUGAUCCUCCUGCCUCAGCGUCCCAAAGUGUUGGGAUUACAGGUGUGAACCACCAUGCCUGGCCCAGGAUAGCACUUUUUCCUUUCUUCUGCUCUCAGUUGGUUGGACCACUGGUUGCAUCUCUUCCCACUCUCCCUGAAAGGCACAGAACUAUCAGACAGAAGACAAGGUAGUUCUCAAGAAGUACCAGGCAGCUGUGUCUGCUAGAGGCUUCCUCAGCAAAGCCCCAUCUUGUGGACAACCUCUCAGGAAUUGCAGGUGGUGUGGGAGUGGCUGACAGAGGAGGGAUCCAUAUGUCUUAGACCAAAGCCACCAGUCAGGCCUUGCCACCAUAUAGAACCUUCCCUUUAGAAUAUAUUUAUUUGGAAUUUUACUUAUAGCUGCAAAUAUAUCAUUGGCUACUAUACCCAAGCAUCAACUCAAGGAACAUUUGGUUUUCUGGUGAGCACAGCUGAAGACCAACCAACUAGUUACUGAUCCAGAUGAGGGAAGAGAACAUUUAUUCAGUCAUUCUGUUAUGCUAACUAUUCAUUUUCUCAUGAAAAUGUAGUCUUUGGCUGGGCAUGGUGGCUCAUGCCUGUAAUCCCAGCAUUUUGGGAGGCCAAAGCGGGCAGAUCAUGAGGUCACGAGAUCGAGACCCUCCUGGCUAACACGGUGAAACCCCAUCUCUACUAAAAAUACAAAGAAUUAGCCGGGCAUAGUGGCAGGCACCUGUAGCCCCAGCUACUCGGGAGGCUGAGGCAGGAGAAUGGCGUGAACCUGAGAGGUGGAGCUUGCAGUGAGCUGAGAUUGUGCCACUACACUCCAGCCUGGGCGACAGAGCAAGACUCCGUCUCAAAAGAGAAAAUGUUGUCUUUGCCAGGCAGUGUGGUAGGCCCAAGAGAUAUAGCAAUUAGAGUUGACUAAGACAGUGUCCCUAUCCUGUUCUUGAGCUCCAGUUCUAGUGGGAGUUCUUGAGCUUGGUAAGAUGAUGUGAGUCCAUCAGUGGCCCAGGACUCUAAGCAUGUAUGUUUUAGUCCCAGCUGUAAAUGAGGAUUCCAUUAACCCCAUCUUCUCCAAUGUAUGGAGGAUGCAAGAAGCUUUAAAAUGUCCUUUUCUCACAGUGACUUCCCUUGACCAUGCCUUAGUUUCCUCAGCCAGAAAUUGGAGACAGCAAGAGCACUUAUGCCUGAGUUGGUGAGAUGGAAUGAUGUAUCAUAUCUCUUCCCCUUUUAUUAACCAGAUCGUUUACCAGAUUGUACCUGGUGAUGCUGGCAGCCAGCCCUCUUCCGGCCCCUAUUUCUGCUUACCGUGUUACCAGAGAGCCUGGGGGUCUGGAUCCUAUCUGGCCCCGUCAGGGUGGAUUACCAAAUGAGCAGUUCUCUUGCCCCAGUCCCUUUCCUGUGCUAUAAAUAAGCCCCAUGUUUAUUUUCUUAUGUUAUUGAAAUGAGCACUUGUGAUUUGGGCCUCUUUUGAGGAGUCCAGAGAGCGUCCAUCCGGUGCCUGGUGAGGGCCCUGCAUGGCUGGCUGCUGUCUGAAGCUAUUUGGAGUCCUCUCCCUGUGUUUUCUAUGUGGCUUAAUUUCAAUAGAAAGGGUUAUAUGCAACCCUGUAUCUGCUGAUUUUCAGGUUUCAACUUUCUGCCAGCGUCACUGCCUGCUUAGAAGUAAAGUUAUGUUUCUCAUUAAGGGGAUAACAGCCACAAUUGAGGUAAUUAACGAAAAUUGUACAUUGGUGGCAGCACCUCCUAUAGGAUUUCCAAUAGUCUUUCUCUAGUAGAUCAUUGGGGGCUCACCUUGAUCUCCUCUCUUCUGUCUACCCUGCACCAAAAUACCUUGUCCUGUUUUCUGGAUAUAGUUCCAAUAAUUUUUUUCCUAACAGCCUUUUUGUCACCAGUUGGUUUGAUAUCUUACAACUUGGCCAAAUGAGGGUUCCAUUAACUCCAUCUUGUCUAAUGCAUGGAGAAUUCAAGGAUUUUUUUUUUCUCUUUUCAUAGCACCUUCCAGUUGCCAGUUGUACCCUGGCCCUUCUUUGGAAGUCAUAAUGAUGAAUAUCCAUUAAUAAGAGAUUGAUGCUCUUUCAACUCUCAUGUCAUCUAUACCAUCUCAGUGGAGAGGAUGACUUUGGAUGAGGUUGGAAUAGAAAGGAAACAUUUGGAAGUCCACUGCAGUGUAUUAUAUGCUGUGUGGAAGUCUGGGGGUUAGGAAAUACCUGGAGGGAGAACUUCCUAAGAAAUGAUUUUUGGUUCUUUUAGGCCUUAACAGCACAAUAAAAGUAUCCCAUGAGACCAUUAUGAGCAGGACACGACAUUGUUUCACACCUUGGGCUGUGACUAUUUACUUCUCGGUACAGAUUACUCUGGUUAAAUCACUCAGUAAAGAAAUCUUUUCAUGCUCACAAUCUGAACCUGAAGGCUAUUACUGAAGAGAAUUGCAUCUGACAACAAAAUUUAAUUUACUUCCAGAGAAAGGACCAGAAGAAAGUAAAUUUUCAUUUAUGUUUUUAAGUCUAUUGUCUUAAAAAGAUUCUUUUCCCUUAAAAAAUAAAAAAACCUGAUGUGAUGGGUUCCUUCAGUCAACAAAUACUUAUUGAGCAGUUAUUGUGUGCCAGAUACUGUUCUUGGUGUGAGGAUAUGGCACUGAACAAAACAAUGUACCUACUUUCGUCAAGCUUACAUUCUAAUGAGGAAGAUAACCAAAACAAGUGACUGAAUAUAAUUUCAAAUGUCAAUAAAUGCUGUGAAGAAAAUAAA